GCGCCUUGCUGCCCCAUGCAGCCCUGAGCCCCACAGCAAGUCUGCCAUGGGCCGCGGGGCCCGUGUCCCCUCGGAGGCCCCGGGGGCAGGCGUCGAGCGCCGCUGGCUUGGAGCCGCGCUGGUCGCCCUGUGCCUCCUCCCCGCGCUGGUGCUGCUGGCCCGGCUGGGGGCCCCGGCGGUGCCGGCCUGGAGCGCAGCGCAGGGAGACGUCGCUGCGCUGGGCCUCUCGGCGGUCCCCCCCACCCGGGUCCCGGGCCCACUGGCCCCCCGCAGACGCCGCUACACGCUGACUCCAGCCAGGCUGCGCUGGGACCACUUCAACCUCACCUACAGGAUCCUCUCCUUCCCGCGGAACCUGCUGAGCCCGCGGGAGACGCGGCGGGCCCUAGCUGCCGCCUUCCGCAUGUGGAGCGACGUGUCCCCCUUCAGCUUCCGCGAGGUGGCCCCCGAGCAGCCCAGCGACCUCCGGAUAGGCUUCUACCCGAUCAACCACACGGACUGCCUGGUCUCCGCGCUGCACCACUGCUUCGACGGCCCCACGGGGGAGCUGGCCCACGCCUUCUUCCCCCCGCACGGCGGCAUCCACUUCGACGACAGCGAGUACUGGGUCCUGGGCCCCACGCGCUACAGCUGGAAGAAAGGCGUGUGGCUCACGGACCUGGUGCACGUGGCGGCCCACGAGAUCGGCCACGCGCUGGGCCUGAUGCACUCACAACACGGCCGGGCGCUCAUGCACCUGAACGCCACGCUGCGCGGCUGGAAGGCGUUGUCCCAGGACGAGCUGUGGGGGCUGCACCGGCUCUACGGAUGCCUCGACAGGCUGUUCGUGUGCGCGUCCUGGGCGCGGAGGGGCUUCUGCGACGCUCGCCGGCGGCUCAUGAAGAGGCUCUGCCCCAGCAGCUGCGACUUCUGCUACGAAUUCCCCUUCCCCACGGUGGCCACCACCCCACCGCCCCCCAGGACCAAAACCAGGCUGGUGCCCGAGGGCAGGAACGUGACCUUCCGCUGCGGCCAGAAGAUCCUCCACAAGAAAGGGAAAGUGUAGUGACUGGUACAAGGACCAGGAGCCCCUGGAGUUCUCCUACCCCGGCUACCUGGCCCUGGGCGAGGCGCACCUGAGCAUCAUCGCCAACGCCGUCAAUGAGGGCACCUACACCUGCGUGGUGCGCCGCCAGCAGCGCGUGCUGACCACCUACUCCUGGCGAGUCCGUGUGCGGGGCUGAGCCCGGCUGAUAAAGCACUUUCUCUCUGA